CCUUCGCAGCCAUUUUCUGUCCAACCAAACAGCCGAUUGGAGACGGGAGCCAACCAGGGCUGCAUUGGAGGUUUGUGUCUCGCUUCGGCCAAUGAUCGCUCCUAAACCGACUCCACUUUAGCUCGAAUGAAAUGUCCGUCUCCUCCCGGCGCCGUCCCCGCCGCCAACGCCGCCGCGGCCGGGGGCACUAGCCUCCCGCCCUCCCGCGCGGGCCGAGGCCGGGCCCCGCGCCUGCGAGGCCGCUCCCGCAGCGGGCCGGGCCGGGGAGCGGGCGCGGGGCCGCGGCGCGGCUCUUUGUGCGCCGGGCUGAGGAGCGGCGGGACGCGGGCCAGGCCACCUCACCCUCGCCGCCGUUGAGCUCCGGGCCCGGGGCCGAGGAGGGGCCGCGGGGCUGCGUCGGGGCCCCGCUCUCGACGGCGUCCCGGGCCGGCUCCAUUUUGUGCGGGGAGCCGGCCGAGGGGCGGGAGACGCGGCCCGGGCCCUGGCCCCGUAGCCCCGGCGGCGGCGCGAGUCCCCGGGGGCGCCCUCCUCCCGCCCGCGGGGCUGUGGCGGGGCCCGGCGCUUUGUCUGCCCGCACAUCCCGGGGGCCGCGCGGCGGGUGGGAGGCAGGCGUUGGGCGCGGGGCCGGGGCGGCCGGGCGAGUCAGGGGAUGCGCUCUGGGGGCGGCCUCCUGGCACUCGCAGGGCUGACAGGUCGCCGGGACCAGGCCGUGGGGCCGGGGCCACCCAGGCACCUGCGUGGGGAGGAAGGCAUGGCUUUAGCUUCCCCGCAGCCUGGUUUGCGCGUAAAGAAUGCAGCCAUCUGGCGGUUUGCGGUCCCUGUACUUGCCCCGAAGGUGGGAAGGAAGCCCUUCGGAUUGGACUAAGGUUUUAAUCAUUAGUGGUGGGAGGCGGGAGGAUAUGCAGGGCCUUAAAGAACGGUAGUCUUAGAGAACAAAGAAUUACAGAGCACCCACAAAUCGUAAUCUCGCCCAAAGCACUCUAACAGGAUAAUUUAAACAAGGUUGAAAUCACAAAGAUUAGACACCUUUUUAGAUAGGUGUUCUUCAGCACCACUGACAACACGGUUCUGACAGUAUUUCAUGACAAUGGAUGGUGACAGUUCUACAACAGAUGCUUCUCAACUAGGAAUCUCUGCAGACUAUAUUGGAGGAAGUCAUUAUGUUAUACAGCCUCAUGAUGAUACUGAGGACAGCAUGAAUGAUCAUGAAGACACAAAUGGUUCAAAAGAAAGUUUCAGAGAACAAGAUAUAUAUCUUCCAAUAGCAAACGUGGCUAGGAUAAUGAAAAAUGCCAUACCUCAAACGGGAAAGAUUGCAAAAGAUGCCAAAGAAUGUGUUCAAGAAUGUGUAAGUGAGUUCAUCAGUUUUAUAACAUCUGAAGCAAGUGAAAGGUGCCAUCAAGAGAAACGGAAAACAAUCAAUGGAGAAGAUAUUCUCUUUGCUAUGUCUACUUUAGGCUUUGACAGUUAUGUGGAACCUCUGAAAUUAUACCUUCAGAAAUUCAGAGAGGCUAUGAAAGGAGAAAAGGGAAUUGGUGGAGCAGUCACAGCUACAGAUGGACUAAGUGAAGAGCUUACAGAGGAGGCAUUUACUAACCAGUUACCAGCUGGCUUAAUAACCACAGACGGUCAACAACAAAAUGUUAUGGUUUACACAACAUCAUAUCAACAGAUUUCUGGUGUUCAGCAAAUUCAGUUUUCAUGAUCUGAAGAAAUGAUGGAAUGGGGAGUGUAGAGAAAUGAGAGUCUGUAUGAUUCUGGAACAGAGACAUCAGAAGGAAAGACUGGUGAAAAGAUGUAUCUUUGUAUAUUAAUAGCUGUAAUGUAGCUUCCUGAUGCUUGACUAAUUGAGGUGUUAAUUCUGACUUGAGAAUCUUUUUCAUGAAUGAUUUUAAAGAAAAAUUUGGAUUUUAAAGGUAUUAAAAUAUUUUUGUUUUGUACGAGAGUUUGUUGCUCUGUAUGACUCCUGUAUGCAUUGUAUAUUGCAAUUUAUUACUGUCAGAGAUUUGUAGACAGUUUCUUAUUUUCAUAUUGAAUCAUGUUACUUUUGUAAUUCAAGUAAGCGGCUGGGUUAAUUCAUGAUGUUUGCCCUUUUAAUAAAAUAUAAGGGUAGAGUUCAUUUUGAAUGCAAGUUGCCUUUAUUAUAAAUUUGAGUUUGUCUUGGUUAUACCUUGCAUGAUAACCUAGCUAGAUUUCUAGCAUUUGCUGUAUUUAUUAAAAUUAUUAUUUUUUUGGUAAAACAUUAAUAGUUUAAGCAGCAUCAUUUUUUUAAAAAAUGUAAUUGAAUAAGUGUGAAUGCAGAAGCAAAUAUUGUCUGCCCUGUUAAACUUGGUGCCCAUUAACAGUGUUUACACUGUUCAUCGUGCCUGUUAAUGUAGUUUUAGUUACUGGAGCUUUUUUAAGACUAGAUUUGGUUUUGAGUUACAUUUUUAAGAAUGUGGGAAUAUAUUUAAGUUUAAUGUAGUCCUAGUGCUCUUGAAAUGGUGCCCCUUUCAUUUGGUACAUGAUUUUUUUUCAAAUCAUAUCUUCAAGUACUAUAGUAUUCUCUUACAGAAGAGGAGUUUUAUAGUCUGAUGGUAAAUGUCUUCAUUUUACCUUUUUAAUUGAAAUGUCAAGUUUCCUGUUACACUAUGGAAACCAAGAAACAUCAGACAUCAUUGCGUGUACAGACCUUUUGCAUGGGUGAGUGGAUGAAAUGGAGAACAGAGUGAGUGCUGUGAACGGUGUGAAAUAGAAGCCAACUUCUAGUAUGCUGUCUUCAUCUCUGCAAUAAACUAAACGUAAAUAAUGUAACUUUGUAUAAUUUAGUAGUAUGUACUUGGAUUGUUUCUUUUUGAAAAGUGAGGAUUUGUAUUUUCUCAUCUAUUCUUUUUGGUGUUAAUUAACUUGAGGGAUUUCUUUUUUAAGUUUUUAAUAUCAAAAAUUGCUAUUGUAUAGUUUGCCUAAAAGGAAGUUGGAGUGAAUAUCAUCUUUGAAGGACACUCAAAUUUAUAAGGUAGAAGCAAUUUCCCAGAUAUAGGCUGAACAGAAACAUUUACUUUGCCAGAAGGAGCCUUUAGGAGUAUAUGUGGGCUAAUCAGAGGUUAAUAAUGUCCUCAUCUCCUACUCUCCAUUUAAAAAACAAACUUCAUUGUAGUAAAUUCAAAUAGGAAAAAAUGGGGGAGUAGUUAAGCAAAAUCAACAGUCAUCCUACUAUGUUGAAAGAACCAAUGUUAAUAUUUUGAUAAAUAUCAUUUGUCCUUUUACUUUGCUAAAUAUGUAUAUUUUUAUAAAAAUGGGCUCAUAUUGUGCAUACCAUUUUGUAACCUGCUUUUUUCACUUAACAAUAUAUUGGGAACAUCUUUUCCAGGUCAUGCAUAGUCUUCUGCAUCAUUUUUAUUGGUUUAUUAUUCUGCUGUAUGACUCAAUCAUAAUUCAUUUAAUCUUCUAUUGGAUAUUUUGACUAUUUACAUCUUUUCACAGUUAUAAACAGCACUUCACUGAAUCCCAUGUACAUCCAUGACUGUUUUCUUAAAUUCUUUGAAUUGCUGGGUUACCAAAUAUGCAAAAUUUUAAGGCUUUUGAUACUUCGUUAUGAGUGUAUUUUUGAGAUAUUUUCCACUUGAUCCAAGCAGUGUGUCACUAUAUAACUGAUAAAAGCACUUGGUCUUUGAUUAUCAGAUACUGUCUCUAAAAUUAUUUUAAAGAUUAAUAUUUGUUCAAGUAGAGAAUGAAGAUAAAAAAGGAAUUUGAGGCCAGGUAUGGGGUGUCUCAUGCCUAUAAUUCCAGCACUUUGGGAGGCCAAGGCAGGCAGAUCACUUUGAGGUCAGGAGUUUGAGACCAGCCUGGCCAACAUGGAGAACCCCCCGUCUCUACAAAAAAUACAAAAUUAGCAGGGUGUGGUGGUGCACACCUGUAGUCCCUUACUCCCUGGUGGCUGAGGCAUUAUCCCUUGAACCUGGGAGGCAGAGCCUAAAGUGAGCCGAGAUCGCGCCACUGCACUCCAGCCUGGGUGACACAGCAAGACUCUUGUCUCAAACAAACAGGAAUUUGAGUAAAUUUUAAAUUAGUAUAUACUACAACAAAUUUCCAAACUUCAUAAUUUGCUAGUAGUGCUAACUAAAAUUUUACACCAGGUAAAAUCAGGUCACCUUUUUUAUGUAUUGACUUCAUUGUUGGACUUCAUACUCUGAUGGGAAAGAAAAUGGACAUUCUGAAUGUGUCAGGUGCAUAAUAUCCUAAUUUAUGCUUGUCAGAGCUGGGGUCUCUGUCUUCCUUGGCCCAUGUUGCAUUUAACUGAAUGUCAUGUUUUCUCCUCUGGAACUUCUUAUGUAUGCAAGCUCCCAUGUUAACCUAUCAUAAAAAUGUUUUUUAUAA